GAGUCGGCCAUCAUGCUGGCCCCGGAGGCCGUUAGCUUAGUCAUGGCUCUAAAUAUGUACCUGCAAUCGGAUGUUGAGGAUCACCGAGCCCGCGACGUAGAAGUACGGGAAGUUCAUGCGCAGCUGCCAGGCCAGCUCGAAGAAGGCGAGCAGGGUGCGGGAGAGCCCCUUGCAGAAGACGCCGUACGAGGUUCUCCAGCAUUUGGCUCAAGGCCCCAAGGGCACAUGUGACAAGAAGGCGCCAGCUUUUUAAACAUUGGAAGUUCUUCUGUGUCAGUUCUGUGACAGAACAUUUACUUAACACAUCAUGAAGGCUAGUUUGGAUGUGGAGGGGAAUAGACUCCAUCUAUCCAUAUGAGAGUUGGAGUCUCACUCUGUUAUCCAGGCUGGAGUUCAGUGGUAGGAUCAUGGCUUACUGCAGUCUGGAACUCCUGGGCUCAAACCAUCCUCCCACCUCAGCCUUCUGCUGCAGAAGAAUAUUUUGCCUGCUGGAACCUGCUGUAUCUACUCAAGAGUGGAAGUUUUCACAGAAGAUGCAGCACACUGUCAAAAUAUCCGGAGACGCCAGCACCAAAGCCCACAGAGGAGUUAAAAGUGUGAUCACUUUCUUCCUACUCUAUGCCAUUUUCUCUCUGUCUUUUUUCAUAUCAGUUUGGACCUCUGAAAGGUUGGAGGAAAAUCUAAUUAUUCUUUCCCAGGUGAUGGGAAUGGCUUAUCCUUCAUGUCACUCAUGUGUUCUGAUUCUUGGAAACAAGAAGCUGAGACAGGCCUCUCUGUCAGUGCUACUGUGGCUGAGGUACAUGUUCAAAGAUGGGGAGCCCUCAGGUCACAAAGAAUUUAGAGAAUCAUCUUGAAUAUAUUAGAAAAAAAAUAGCUCCUAAGAAAUUCUUGUAUGUUAUAUAAAUUUAUACUUCCUUAAGAUUCUUUCAUUGUGUAUAACUUUGUGAAUUUUACAAAGAUAUGCUUGGAAUCAACACCAUCCAAACAUAUCACAAAUUAGGAUAUAUGAAAGUAUGUAUAUUACCAUACAGAGAAGAAUGCGAAUACUAUAAAGAGUUCUUAUACAAACAGAUAAUAUAGAUUUUGUAUCAAUCAUUCACCUUUUUUGAGAUUUUUAAAUGAGAAAACCUAUAAUGUAUAAAAUACAUGUGUGUAUGUAUGUAUGUGACACAGUUACUAAAAAUAGGCUUCUUAAACUUACAUCUCAAUCUGGUAGAUAAAGUACAUAAAAGAAUAUGGAAUUUUAGUACCUAUAUUAAGUGUUUUUAAUUUUUGUAUAAUAUUUAGUACCUGAUUAGCGUGUAUGCAAAAAAGUAAUUUGCUUCGUUUGUUGAAUUAGAAGCCAGCUGCCUUACUAAACUACCACAUUUGCUUUGCUCAUUCUCUUGGCUUUGCAGAUAGAAAAUUAUAUCAUCUGCAUAUAGUGACUUAUAAUGAUUAUUUUACUUCUCCAUUUUACUACUUGUAAUUCUUUUUUGGUAUCAGUUGUAUAAUGAAAUGGUUUGAACAUUCAAAGUGUUAAGUAAUCCUGAUCGUAACUGCUGUCUUUGCAAAUGGAGUGUUUUCUAGUGUUUUAACAAUAAACGUAAUACUGACUCUAGCUUUGAGAUAAAUUCUUUUAAAAAUAUUCUUCAGGGAGAAUAUUUGUUUCCUAUCUUCCUGUGUAUAGUAUUGUAAUAAAAUCUCUGUUAAAAACUA